CUGGGCCGCCCGUCGUACCUGAUGGUAGGAGGCAGUAGUUCCCCGCUUCCCUUCCGCGGGAGGGAGAGUUAGCUAGCCAUCCAAGAAAACACCAUGAAAGAUAACGAUAUCAAGAGACUACUGUAUACCCAUCUUUUAUGCAUAUUUUCAAUUAUCCUAAGUGUCUUCAUUCCAUCACUCUUCUUGGAGAACUUCUCAAUAUUGGAAACACACUUGACAUGGUUGUGCAUCUGUUCUGGUUUUGUAACUGCUGUCAAUCUAGUACUAUAUUUAGUAGUGAAACCAAAUACAUCCUCUAAAAGAAGUUCAUUAUCACACAAGGUAACUGGAUUUUUGAAAUGCUGUAUCUACUUUCUUAUGUCUUGUUUCUCCUUUCAUGUAAUUUUUGUUCUGUAUGGAGCACCACUGAUAGAGUUGGCAUUGGAAACAUUUUUAUUUGCAGUUAUUUUGUCUACUUUUACUACUGUGCCUUGCUUAUGUUUGUUAGGACCAAACCUCAAAGCAUGGCUAAGAGUGUUCAGUAGAAAUGGAGUUACAUCCAUAUGGGAGAAUAGUCUCCAGAUCACUACAAUUUCUAGCUUUGUAGGAGCAUGGCUUGGAGCACUUCCUAUUCCACUGGAUUGGGAAAGACCAUGGCAGAAGCAGAUAGCAAGGUAAUUUUUGCAGCAGCGGCCUGUGUUAUCAAGAAAGCUCACAAACAUCAGAUUUUUCGUCUUGUAUCACAAUAAGAUAAAGCUGAUAUGCUAGGUAAAGCACUGUGAGGUAAGUGCUCUUUUUAUACCCAUUUUACAGAUGAGGAAACUGACACCUAGAGGGUAUGUAACAUUCCCAAGGUCACUGAACUUACAGUGAUGACUGUAUCUUUAUCUUAAUAUUAAUGACUUUGUAGUAUGCCAUUAUAUACUUUAUAACUUAUUUAACAAAUUCACUAUUGAUCAUUUAGAUUAUUGCCAGUAUUUUGUGAUAAUAAACACUGCUGUGAUAAAAUCUUUGAAUCUAUAGCUUCUUGAAUUUUUCUAAUUAGGUUCACAGAGUAAUUACUCCCAAAAAGAAUUAUGGUAUUAAAAAAUAAAUGUGCUUUCUUUUUCCAACAUGAAGAUAAUUUUUUUCUGAUCACGAAGAUAAUGUAUAUUUAUUUAGAAAAUUAAAGCAAUAUUAGUAAUUCUAAGGAAGAAAGUAAAAAUUACUUUCCUCCCCAACCACCCAGAGGAAACCUCCAUUUGCUUUUGGUGAUAAUUUUUGCAGCUGUCUCUCUCCAUGCCUGUAACUAUAAUAUUCAUGUUGUUUUUAAUCUGCUUUUUCCCCUCAGCAGUAUAUUAUGGAGCUCAUUCUAUGUCAAUGAAAACUUACAUAUAUGUAAUAUUCGAUUAUUUGUGUAAAAUAUUGUACCAGUUUUUUAUUAAAGAACAUUUAGGUCA